AGUCAGCGGCGCCUAGUGAGAGUCAGGGGGGCCCGGCCCGCGCCCUCCCCGCCCAGCCGCCUCCCCGUCGACGCCCAGGGCUGGGGCGAGCCAGGCUGCCUUUCGAACUUGGGGGGCUUCUCCUCUUGUCUCCCACUGGUGCUCUGGCUGUGAAUCCAUCCAGGGGCCAGGAUGACAAUCCGACACCAAGGCCAGCAGUACAGGCCGAGGAUGGCAUUUCUCCAAAAGAUUGAAGCGCUCGUGAAGGACAUGCAGAACCCAGAGACAGGGGUCCGAAUGCAGAACCAGAGGGUCCUGGUCACCAGCGUUCCUCAUGCCAUGACAGGAAGUGAUGUUCUGCAAUGGAUCGUCCAGCGGCUUUGGAUCUCCAGUCUGGAGGCACAGAACUUGGGCAACUUUAUUGUCAGGUAUGGCUACAUUUACCCCCUGCAAGACCCCAAGAAUCUCAUUCUCAAGCCUGAUGGCAGCCUCUACAGAUUUCAGACACCGUAUUUCUGGCCCACCCAGCAGUGGCCAGCUGAAGAUACCGAUUACGCCAUCUAUCUGGCCAAGCGAAAUAUCAAAAAGAAAGGGAUUUUGGAAGAAUAUGAAAAGGAAAAUUACAAUUUCUUGAACCAAAAAAUGAACUAUAAGUGGGACUUUGUCAUUAUGCAGGCCAAAGAGCAGUACAGGGCUGGAAAGGAGAGGAACAAAGCAGACAGAUAUGCCCUGGACUGCCAGGAGAAGGCAUACUGGCUGGUGCACCGAUGCCCUCCUGGAAUGGACAAUGUGCUGGACUACGGCCUGGACCGAGUGACCAAUCCGAAUGAAGUCAAGAAACAAACAGUCGUUGCUGUCAAAAAAGAGAUCAUGUAUUACCAACAGGCCUUGAUGAGGUCCACAGUGAAGUCUUCUGUGUCCCUGGGAGGGAUUGUGAAAUACAGUGAGCAGUUCUCAUCCAACGAUGCCAUCAUGUCAGGCUGCCUCCCCAGCAACCCCUGGAUCACCGAUGACACCCAGUUCUGGGACUUAAAUGCCAAAUUGGUGGAAAUCCCAACCAAGAUGCGAGUGGAACGAUGGGCCUUCAACUUCAGCGAAUUGAUCCGAGACCCCAAAGGUCGACAGAGCUUCCAGUACUUCCUCAAGAAAGAAUUCAGUGGAGAGAAUCUGGGAUUCUGGGAAGCCUGCGAGGAUCUGAAGUAUGGAGAUCAGUCCAAAGUCAAGGAGAAAGCAGAGGAGAUUUACAAGCUGUUCCUGGCCCCGGGGGCGAGGCGCUGGAUCAACAUAGAUGGCAAAACCAUGGACAUCACAGUGAAGGGGCUGAAGCACCCCCACCGCUAUGUGCUGGACGCCGCACAAACCCACAUUUACAUGCUCAUGAAGAAGGAUUCUUAUGCUCGCUAUUUAAAAUCUCCGAUCUAUAAGGACAUGCUGGCCAAAGCUAUUGAACCUCAGGAAACCACCAAGAAAAGCUCCACCCUCCCUUUUAUGCGGCGUCACCUGCGCUCCAGCCCAAGCCCUGUCAUCCUGAGACAGCUGGAAGAGGAAGCCAAGGCCCGAGAAGCAGCCAACACUGUGGACAUCACCCAGGUCAUGAGCAAGCUGGACCGCAGGAGCCAACUCCAAAAAGAGCUGCCUCCUAAAUAAAUCUGUGAUUCCUGGGGGUGGGGUCAUGCACUUGGGAGAGGCAAAUGAAGAAGGGUAGGGUCAGAGUCUAGAAGGUUCCAUUCCCCAUUUGUGGAGGUCAUCAGGUUCAUCCCAUACUCCUCUAACUUUCUUCAUGGGGGACUUCCUAAUACCACAGCAACCAGAGCUUGUUCUCCCAAGCCCACUCAUCAGGGGACAGGGUGGGCGAAGGCGGUGGGUGGGAGAGGGGAUCACCUGACUCAAUUGCUGUGUGGCUGCCUAUUGUACCUUAGAGAGUUCUUAGGGGAACUAUGAACUUUUUCAGUAAGAGCCAGGGGGAAAAAGCUGUCUCAGUGAGAGCCAUAGGGAAAAGUGGUACACAAAGCUCUCACUGAGAGAGAGCUUUGUCUACCACUCUCUGCUUUGGAAAAUUAAAAAGAAGGCCUCUCCCCAUACCCAAGGCCUAGUGUUUUUCAGGGAGAUUUGUUUAAAAUAGCUUUAUGAAGCUCCUCAUCCUAUCUCUCUAAUUUAGACUAUUGUUUCCAAAUCAUUCUGAGGAUCCGCCGAGGGGCUAGUUGCAGGGAAGUACUUUCUCUGAACUCCCCUGCUAUGCCUGCCUGGAAAGACCCUGCUGAGACGUUUCUCCUGUUGAGUUUGUUCUUAGUCAUAAUUACUGGAGGGUUGAUGGGCUCUCUUCUUCCCAUCUCCCCAUCCCCUUGUCCAUGCUGGGGAAAUAAGCGGCUUGCGGGAAUGAAGGACUCAAAUGGCCCUCUGAGGAGCAUCUUUUUGGCUAAAGAACAAAGGCAUUGAUGUCUUCAUUCAUGGGAAGAGGAUGGUAGACAUCGAGAUGAGUGAGGAUCAGAGAUGAUACUCUCUAGGACAUUUUCUAGAUGUUGAUUCUUCCCUCUUCUGUAGGUGUAGACGAGGUCAGCCCUGUGGUCAGGACUGGGGGAGAGGACAGUUCUAACUGACCUUGGGGGGUUUAGAAGGUCAUUCUCGAAGUUAGGCUCACUCCUUACACUUGUGCAAGAAUGCAACAGAGAUAGAGCACAGAAGUGAGCAAGAGACCAGCCUGACCAAGCAGGAAUACUCACUCAUUCAGCACGUCUAUUGAGCACCUACUAUGUGCAAACAUCGGUGAAUAAAACAGACGUGGUUCUCUCUCAUGGAGCUUCUUCUAGUCUAGGACUGAGACAAAAUAAUUAAACAAACUAUCAGGUAGCUAUUGCUGUGUGACAAUCAACCAGAAAAAUAGAGCAACAUUCAGCAAGUGUUCAUUGUUCAUGCAUGUGGGGUCAUCUGUGUGGCUCUGUGGAUCUUGGCUGGGUCCACUCAUCUGUCUAGGAGUGUUGCAGUGGCCUAGGCUGAGAUGAGUGAGAUGAGUUUUCUCUGCUUCAUGUACCUCUCUUCUCCCAGCAGUCUUGCCUAGGCAGAAUCCCAUGCUGAAGACUGAAUUGCAAGGGAGCAAGUAGAAACACACAAGGCUUCACAUAGUCUCUUCUACUUUAUUUUAUUGGCCAAAGAAAGUCAUAAAGCCAGCCUAGAUUCAAGGGGCAAGGAAAUAGACUCUACCUCUUUAGUGAGAGAAAUUUCAAAGUCUCAUGGCGAAAGAUGGAUGAAAUUUCAAAGUCUCGUUGCAAAAGACAGGGAAAGUUGAAGAAUGAGGGCCAUUGUUGUAAUUAACAACACAAAUGCCUGCCCAAGGAUUAUAAAGGAAAUUAAUGUGGUACUGGGAUAGGAAAGAUGGGAUGUGUGUAGGCUAUGCCCCUGCUAGCUGGUGACAGAGAAGCAGGGAAUGAGAAAGAGUUGGCCAUAAGAGCAUGUGGACCAGGCAGGGAGAACGUUCUGGGGAGAGAGGGCUGUGUGGGCAAAGGCUCAGAGCUGGGAAGUAGCUCAGAGUGAACCGAAAGGCCAGGUGAGUGAAGCCUGCUGGGUGAGGGGGAAACUGUGCAAGAUGAGUUUAGAGAGUGGGCAGGGGCCAGAUCAUUGAUGACCUUCAAGGCUGUUCUAAGGAGUCUGUGGUCACUGGUUUCAUGUUAGCAAAAUGAUUCUAGCCCAGAAGAGGGACACUUACACUUUCCAUUUGCACUGGUUGCAGACCAGUUUCCACUCUGAAAGUGCAUGGAGGGAUAUGCUUUGCUCAUCUCUCUUCUGGAGAAUCUUGGAGUCUUCCCACUCUGGAAGGUACCCCAAGUAGAAAUGUAAACCAUUGUAAACUGGGUGACACGAGAGGAGGGACUGUAUUUAUCUCAUUCAUUACUUGGAGCCUGAUUCCUGACACCCAGGGGGUUCUGCACCAACAUGAAUGACAUGAGUGGAUGAAUGAAUGAAAGAAUGAAUGAAUGAAUGAAAAGAGCCCUGGAUUUGGAGAAAGCCUCCUGGUUCCUGUUCCUGGCUCUAGCACUAGUCAUGUAGCCUUGGACAAGUCACUUAACCUCUCUACAUCCUUAUUUGUGAAAUGAGGUAUCAGGACCAGCUCUAAACUUCUCUAAACAGACUUUGUGAAUUCCGACUGGGAACCCGGGCUGGGGCAUCCAUUUUACUUGAAGAUUUGGAAUGGGAGGAAAAUUAGGUAAUUUCUAAAAGUUUCACAUUAAAAUAAUCAUGAAAAUAUUAUGAAA